CCCAUUGAAACUCCCUUACCAACAGCAAAAUCAGCCACUUGACUUCUCUGUUGUCCAAUAACAUUCUCUUUCCAAUUCAUAAAUUAAGCAUGAGCCUCAGAGGUUUGAACAUAAGUCAAGGACACAAUGGAAAAACUUUAAAAGAUAUGAUUCUUUGAAUCUGACUUUUCUCUCCAAAAGCAGAGCAAAGACACUGCGAUAUUUAGCAUAGCAAAGGGCUUAACUUUUAAACAAGAUUUUCAAGAAUUAAUGCCAGUAGUCUUCUGUUAUGCACUAUAUCUAAUAGCAUCAAAUUUGUAGUUGGAGUUUUGGGAUCAAAGGAACUAGGUAUAUCAAAUGCUUCAGAGUUAAAAUAAUCAUCUCAAUGACAGAAACAACAAAGACUAACUGAAAUCUGAAAAACGUGAACAAUGCAACAAACUGCAAAAACUACAACCGCAUGGGAAGUUUCUGCACUGCAUUCUAGGUGUUUAGGAAGACAACAAAAUAAAUAUCCCAGUGCUUUCACAUGACAUGGUUUAAAACCAAAGAGAAUAAAGAGGAUGAUUGAAUGGAGAUGGAAAACUGCACCAGGGUAAAAGAAUUUAUUUUCCUUGGCCUGACCCAGAAUCGGGAAGUGAGCUUAGUCUUAUUUCUUUUCCUACUCUUGGUGUAUGUGACAACUUUGCUGGGAAACCUCCUCAUCAUGGUCACUGUUACCUGUGAAUCUCGCCUUCACACGCCCAUGUAUUUUUUGCUCCAUAAUUUAUCUAUUGCCGAUAUCUGCUUCUCUUCCAUCACAGUGCCCAAGGUUCUGGUGGACCUUCUGUCUGAAAGAAAGACCAUCUCCUUCAAUCAUUGCUUCACUCAGAUGUUUCUAUUCCACCUUAUUGGAGGGGUGGAUGUAUUUUCUCUUUCGGUGAUGGCAUUGGAUCGAUAUGUGGCCAUCUCCAAGCCCCUGCACUAUGCGACUAUCAUGAGUAGAGACCAUUGCAUUGGGCUCACAGUGGCUGCCUGGUUGGGGGGCUUUGUCCACUCCAUCGUGCAGAUUUCCCUGUUGCUCCCACUCCCUUUCUGCGGACCCAAUGUUCUUGACACUUUCUACUGUGAUGUCCACCGGGUCCUCAAACUGGCCCAUACAGACAUUUUCAUACUUGAACUACUAAUGAUUUCCAACAAUGGACUGCUCACCACACUGUGGUUUUUCCUGCUCCUGGUGUCCUACAUAGUCAUAUUAUCAUUACCCAAGUCUCAGGCAGGAGAGGGCAGGAGGAAAGCCAUCUCCACCUGCACCUCCCACAUCACUGUGGUGACCCUGCAUUUCGUGCCCUGCAUCUAUGUCUAUGCCCGGCCCUUCACUGCCCUCCCCAUGGAUAAGGCCAUCUCUGUCACCUUCACUGUCAUCUCCCCUCUGCUCAACCCCUUGAUCUACACUCUGAGGAACCAUGAGAUGAAGUCAGCCAUGAGGAGACUGAAGAGAAGACUUGUGCCUUCUGAUAGAAAAUAGAAAAAAAAAUCCUCAGCUCUUCAUCACCAAAGAUAUCUUAUAUUUAUUAUUUUUCCCAUGAAGUCAUAUUCAUAUAUUCAAAUAUAUUGUCAAACCAACUACACUUAGUAAUAAUUAAUUUUUCUAUUUAUGUUAGUAAGUAACUGAUAAGCUUCUGGUCAGGGAGAGAUUCACACCUUCUAAUUGAAAAUAAACCAGAGCUCCCUCCUCUUUACCACCAAGAUUUUGUUUCAUGAUUUUUCUUCCAUGGACUCCAAGUUCUGAAAGUGUUGCCUGCUGAAUUGAAUAUAUUUAUUUAGUGAUUGCUAAGUAUUUGUUUUAUUUUCAUAAGUAAUACAUAAAAUUAUAUAUAUACCUAGCAAAUGCAUAUUAUAUAUAGUAAAUCUUCUUAUCUGCAUUUAGUUGACAUAAAUAUUAAUAAUUUAAACAGAGCCUUUGUGAUUCAGAAAAGAGAGGGAAAAUUGUUAGCAAAUGUGUAUAUGAUUUUGCAGUCCAAUUUUAAAGAAAAAUUAAGCCAAAUGCACGCAGACAUUAUCAUUACCUUUCUGCUCCUAUUACAGUAAAUGAAGGUGUGGGGUGUAUCUGAAACACAAUGGAGUUUGGGGAUUGACUUUCUGUAUAAUUUUCAUAAGGUAAACGUAUCCUACAUGAUCCUUAUGAUGGGCAAGGUCAUUACCUUGCCCUUUCUUGAACCCCAAGCUCACUGGCCACCCUACCGCAUUUCCUUGGCACUCUGUGCUUAGGGUUAGCAUUGCACUCAGGACUCUAUUUUGAAAUUUCCUAUUUUCUUGUCUCUUUCUCUUACUGGGCAGUGACUUCCCCAGGAGCAGGGAUUAUGUUUUAUUUACUGUCACAGCAGCUAAAACAUACUAAGACUUCAACAAUAUGUUGCUGAAUAAAUAGCUCAAUGAUUGAAUGUUUUCACUUACUUGAUAUACUCUGUGGCCUGUGAGUUUCUACAAAUGACAAAAACACAUUAAGCUACUUUAAGCUAUG